ACACACGCUCUGUCUGCCUGCCCCGAGUCCCCCGGGAGGCCGCGGGGUUUGGGGAAGUGUUUCUAGGAGACGGCGCUCACCGGCUGCACCUGCGCCGUUGACGCCACCGGGGCCGGCAGACAGACCCGCGGCGCUGGCUGGUGGAGGGAGUUCCCGCUUGCUCUCUGUCGCUGUCACCGCCCUGUUUCUGUAGCCGUAUGGUACGCCUGUGAGACCGGCUGCCGGCUGACGUCUCCUUGCGAUGGAGCAUAUCCGGACGACCAAGGUCGAACAAGUAAAAUUACUUGACCGAUUCAGUACCAGCAACAAGUCAUUAACAGGAACACUGUAUCUUACGGCUACACAUCUAUUAUUUAUCGACUCUCAUCAAAAAGAAACCUGGAUAUUACACCACCAUAUUGCCUCAGUAGAGAAACUUGCUUUGACUACUUCUGGAUGCCCCCUUGUGAUACAGUGCAAGAACUUCAGAACUGUGCAUUUCAUUGUUCCCAGAGAAAGAGAUUGCCAUGAUAUUUACAACUCUUUGCUACAACUGUCAAAACAAGCAAAAUAUGAAGAUCUCUAUGCAUUUUCUUAUAAUCCCAAACAAAAUGAUUCAGAACGACUACAAGGCUGGCAGCUCAUUGAUCUCGCUGAGGAAUAUAAGAGGAUGGGAGUGCCAAACUCACACUGGCAGUUGUCUGAUGCCAACCGGGACUACAAGAUUUGUGAAACUUACCCCAGAGAACUUUAUGUUCCCCGGAUAGCAAGCAAACCAAUAAUUGUUGGUAGUUCCAAGUUCCGGAGCAAGGGAAGAUUCCCAGUUCUUUCCUACUAUCAUCAAGAUAAGGAGGCUGCCAUUUGUCGAUGUAGUCAGCCACUCUCUGGAUUCAGUGCCAGGUGCCUGGAGGAUGAACAUUUGCUUCAAGCCAUUAGUAAAGCCAAUCCAGUCAAUCGCUAUAUGUACGUCAUGGAUACCAGGCCAAAACGUCGCAUGCAGAGCUGGUGGGCUACACAAAAGGACAUUGGCAGAAUUAUAGUGAGGAUUUCUUCAAAAAUCCAGAAUGAUGAGAAAAUAAGAGAAAGCAAUGAGAAAAAGCGACUGAAUGCAAUGGCCAACAGAGCAGCUGGAAAAGGUUAUGAAAAUGAAGACAACUAUUCCAAUAUUAGAUUUCAGUUUGUUGGAAUUGAAAAUAUUCAUGUCAUGAGGUCCAGCCUUCAGAAAUUAUUGGAAGUCAAUGGCACUAAAGGGCUUUCUGUCAAUGAUUUCUACUCCGGUUUGGAGAGCUCGGGAUGGCUUCGCCAUAUCAAAGCUGUUAUGGAUGCUGCAAUCUUCUUGGCCAAAGCAAUAACAGUUGAAAAUGCAAGUGUGUUGGUGCAUUGUUCCGAUGGUUGGGAUAGGACUUCCCAGGUUUGUUCCCUGGGUUCUCUUUUAUUGGAUUCCUACUACAGGACAAUCAAAGGAUUCAUGGUUUUAAUAGAAAAGGAUUGGAUCUCUUUUGGACAUAAAUUUUCAGAGAGGUGUGGCCAGUUGGAUGGUGACCCAAAGGAAGUCUCACCAGUGUUUACUCAGUUCUUGGAAUGUGUGUGGCAUUUGACCGAACAGUUUCCACAAGCCUUUGAAUUCAGUGAAGCAUUUCUUCUUCAGAUCCAUGAGCAUAUUCAUUCAUGCCAGUUUGGAAACUUCCUUGGAAAUUGUCAGAAGGAAAGAGAAGAGCUCAAGUUGAAGGAGAAGACUUAUUCCCUGUGGCCAUUUCUUUUGGAAGACCAAAAGAAGUACUUAAAUCCUCUCUACAGUUCCGAAUCUCACAGAUUUACAGUUUUGGAGCCAAAUACAGUAUCUUUCAAUUUUAAGUUUUGGAGGAACAUGUACCAUCAAUUUGAUCGAACACUGCAUCCUAGGCAGUCUGUAUUUAAUAUAAUUAUGAAUAUGAAUGAGCAAAAUAAACAAUUAGAGAAAGAUAUUAAAGACCUAGAAUCUAAAAUUAAACAACGCAAAAAUAAGCAAACAGAUGGCAUCCUCACCAAGGAAUUGUUACAUUCAGUUCAUCCUGAAUCACCUAACCUCAAAACUUCCCUGUGUUUUAAAGAGCAGACUCUGCUACCCGUAAAUGAUGCUCUUCGAACUAUAGAGGGCAGCAGCCCGGCAGAUAAUCGUUAUAGUGAAUAUGCAGAAGAGUUUUCUAAAUCAGAACCUGCUGUGGUCAGCUUAGAGUAUGGUGUGGCAAGAAUGACUUGUUAGACUCAUAGAGUUUUUUCUGCAAUGAUUGCAGUACAAGAAAAGGAUUAUUGUGAGGAUGGUCUGUAAGCAUAACCAAAAGGAAUUUGUCUAAUAACAAUUUUAGGGUUUAACAGUAGGCUAAUAGUUGAAGGAAGGAUAAUAACUACCCUUGUGAGAGAAAUAAGUCAUUUUAAUUGCAUUUCCAGCAAGGAAUGACAUUCAGUUCUGUAAGAAAUGAGUGGUAUUUGAUGUAUUUACUCAAAACACAAUUUGCACUGUACACUAGUGAAUUGACGUUUAUGAUUUAUGUUAAUUCAGCCAAACAUAAAUAACCUUCCUUAAGUACAAUUUAACUUCAAGAAAACAAAAUUUGACAACAUAGUUUCUUAAUAAAUGAUAUGGCAUGUACUUUCAAUUAUGUAGCUUUGUAACUAUGAAUAUUUACAUAUUUUGCCUUUUAGUGAUAUUUAAUGUUAAAGUGCCAUGAAAAAUAUUUCUAAGAAAGCCUUAAAUUCCCAGUGGAUUCUUUACCCUUAAGUUUUACAGCCUACAACAAGAUUUUUUGUUUUGUUUUUCUUCUGGUCAGCCUUGUUUUGUUUGUAAAGAAUUGUGCUCUCAUUACUGCUGGGGGUGCAUGCUACAAUACUUCUAUAUAAACACUUGUAGAAGUACACUGUUCACGUUUAGCCUGCCCCACUUUUGUAUUCAAAAUUAAUGAAACUGAAGGUUUAUUCUGAUCAUAAUUUGUUUAGUGCUACAUUUGAUAAUUUAUUAUUUACAGCUUAGAAUAUUGAUUUCUUGAAUACGUAUAAGCACAUUUGACUGUCUUUUAUAUAUGGAUUACUGCAUUCCAUUGAUUCUUAUUUUGUGGUUGGCUUUAUUUCUUUCACAACUGUGUAAGUUUAAAGAGCUAAAGCUCUAAAACUGUUCUGAGAAACAAUGAAUAGUACAUGUAUAUGUAUAUUUUUAAACUGCCUUAUUGCUCAAUGAGUUGCUGUUCCUGGAGUAUCUAACUUUCAGUUUACUCAAAAACUUUUGGGUAAAUAAAAAAGGGAAGUACAGAUAGUUUAGGUUGUGCAUGGUUGCAUGAAUUUUGAAGUCAUUUCUAUGUGGAGCAUUAUUUUUCUUCUUGUUAAAUAUAGAAAAAAAAAGAGAUUCUAGUACAAAGUUACUGUUUAACAAAAGCAACAUAAACUCUGGGAAAGAUUUCAUUUUGCCAUGUUAUAUUUACUGUUUAUUCUGUGUACUAGUACAUAUCUUUAAAUUACCAAAAAACAAGAAACAAAACAUAAAAACCCCAAAACUAUCACUUGGAAUUAGCAAUAUCACCCAACUGGCUUUAAAAUUGAAAAUUUAAAUAACAUGGUGGCAUGAAGUACAAUUCGAGUAUUAGGCAAUUUGCAUAGUGUUCCUCAUGCUACUUUCUGUUACACCUCUAUUAUAUUAGUUUUGAAUAUAAACAUCUUUUUCAGACCAAAAAAAACUUUAUUGUAUGAGAGCUUAUCUUAUCCUGUUUAUUUUUCCAAUGCUUUUCUGUAAUACAUUAUGUAAUUUAAAAAAUAUUCCUUUUUAAACAGCAACAGAAAUGCACUAUAAAAUAUAGUAUGUGAUUAACCAAUCCUGCUUCCAUAUUUAAGCACUGGGAAUGGAAACUUAAUCUCUGUGACUACAAAGGGAAGUUUUUGUGCCUUGGUGUUCCAGUCACUGAUUGUGGUUUUAGAAUCUUCUGUGGCUGACUUCUUGUAUUCAACUCUGGUUUAUUAUCUUAAUCUUCAACUUCAGACAUAUAUUUGUGUGUUUAUAUGCUCACAGGUGGACUGAGAAAUCAGUUACAUCUUAAGUGACCUACAGGGUAUAUGUUGGCAAAAGCAGACUGUGUAUAUGUCUUAUAAAGUUGAAUUUAUGUUCAGUGUGUUUGGAAGUGUAUAGCAUGUAAAUUACUUCAUAUAUGAUUUAAAGGUAAUUAAAUGUUCACAUUUUACUUUGAAUGUUUUUCUUCUGGAUAAAACAAAUGGAAUCAAGUUGUAGUUGUUUUUUUUUUCUUCUCACCUAGGCAAGUAGACUUGCCCAUUACAUUAACAUAACAGCAUAAGGUUUGAGGAGUUUAUUUUCCAAAAGUUUGUUGAUAAAUAAUACCUGUUUCAUACAAAAAUAAUUUCCAGAAUAUUUAAAAUAGGUAUAGUGGGCUAAAAGGCCCAUCAGAUGUAGGUAAUAAUGUCAUUAAGUUUUCAUUUUGUUCCUGUCACUUGCUUAUAUUACAAUCACUAUUUUUUUGUGCCCUUGCCAACUUGAUGGAAGGCAGGGUCCAUUGAGUACAAACAUUCGAGGUGAAAUGUCUCUCCAAAGGCAGAUCUGGAUGUAAAUAUGAGGAAGAAAAUAACUGGCUGACAAGAGGAUAAUUUUAUUGAGGGUGUUUUGAAAAGGUCAGCUAGGCUAGAAGUAGCUCAGGGAAUCUUGAGUAAAGAUGAAGGGAACUCUUUUAAAACAAAUUCAAUUUAUUUGGUCGGGUAGCAGAGCAGGGAGGUGGUGUCAGUCAAGCCUGUUUUGAAACAUUUUUUGCAGAAGGUCAGCUUUAAAAUAUUGAAAAAUUUCCAGUUGACAUGCUAAGUUGGAUUAAAUGCUGAUCAUUUAUAAAACUAUAUAGUUGCUGCAAAAGUAAUUGGGGCUUUUGCCAUUGAAAGUGAUGACAAAAACCGCAAUUACUUUUGCACCAACCUAAUACUACAGUUGCAGACUUUUAUUAGUGACGCUGAUCUUCAUUAGUCAAGUUUUAGUUAUUUUGUUGGCUUUUCCAUGUAGAAUUCCAAGUGACAUUAACAUACUUUGAUUAAUUAAAGAAAAUUUGGAGACUGUUUAAGAUAUAUGUCUAGAUAUCAAUGUAAACUAUAAGCUUUAGGAACUUACAUCUAGAAGAAAGCCUGGAAUCUAGAAUAAUUAUCUCAAAAAAAAGUAUAUAUACCAUUGUACUUGAUAUAAGAAAAUGUAAACAUGAAACCUUGACAUUUUAAUAAACAGUAUUUGUGCUACUCUA